CUAACUGUCGGGGCUGGAGCUGGGCAUAUGGGGAAACUGGGGGACCGGCACGGGUUCCAGGCGAGUGGACGGUGGGAUGGAAUCCGACGUGCACACCCAUGUCUCAGGCUUUGUUUGAUGGAGGCUACUGUUUCCACCUCAUGUCGCCGCCCCUUUGCUUAUGGACUCUUGCAGAGUUGGAUUGAGCUCGGGCUGUGUGAUAUAGUGGUUGUUGCAGAAGCCCCAGGGCCACUUUCUGACUAGUACCUUGGGCACCUGACAUCAUCCCUUUGAGUCUCAGUGUCCUCUUCUUUAAAGUGAGGGCGCUCUACCUGAGGAGAUUGCUGUAAGGUUGGAAUGAACCUGCAUGUGUGUGUCAUGUGGGAAGGGAACAGUCAGUGGGGCCUGGGGUUCUCUUGGAGAGCUGGUAACCAGCCUCGUCCCUGAGGCAACAGCCAGAGGGCGCCUGUAGUUUCCCCACGCAUGUCUGUUAGCAGUUACGGCCUCUGGAGGAUCUCCUGUGGGAGGUCCCUACUUCUCACUACAAUCUUUAGAGACUUUGGAGGAUUUCCUAUGGAAGGUCCCCACUUCUCACCACAACAUUCUGGGUUAAAAUGGCCUUGGUAGGGGGAUGGGGGCUGAAGCUGGAUUUUUUUGCUUGCAUUACAAGCUUCUGAACCAAGGACUUCAUGUCACCUGGACUUGGAUUCACAUCCCAGCUCCUUCCUCUCCUAGCUCUAGGACUGUGUAACCUUGGGCAAAUCUCUUAACCUCUUUAAGCCUUAAUUGUUUCAUCUGUAAAAUGAGGCUAACAGUACCUACCUUCCACAAUUGUCGAGAAUUAAAUCAGACAUUGUAGGUAGAGCACUUAAUAGUUGGCAUUCAGCGGCAGCAGUUACUGUUAUGUUAGCAUGUGGAGUGUCUGAGUGUGUGCACAUUGGCUCGAACAGCCUUUUGACAGUGGCACAGUUGGUGCUUGUGUAAGACAGCAGGGCAGAGAAGUCAAAGCCCUCGGUUUUCUAGUCAAACUGGUGGGCCACAACAGUGGUGACCUAAGUCUAAUGAAUCUUCAACUGAACAAGGCAGAUUGAAUCUCCAGGUGAGGACCAAGAGUCUGGGGAUCAGCUGCCUCCACAUUUUUGGGCAUAGAAGGCUGUACAAUACCGCCUUUGUUGUAAGAGCAAGGAACCAUUCAGGGAAGGCACCAUGUGGUAAGGAAUAGAGGCCAGACGUGGAUUAAGAACAAAACAAGAGAAUAGUGUUUGUCUUUAAGUGGAGCCUUGGACUCAAAACAGGAUCUGAGCCCUGAGGAUUUUUUUUUUUUUAAUUGAGAUGGAGUCUUCGUCUGUCACCCAGGCUGGAGUGCAGUGGCGCGAUCUCAGCUCACUGCAACCUCCUUCCCCUGGGUUCAAGCGAUUCUCGUGUCUCAGCCUCCCUAGUAGCUGGGAUUACAGGUGGCUGCCACCACACUCGGCGAGUUUUUUGUAUUUUUAGUGGAAACGGGGUUUCACCACGUUGGCCAGGCUGGUCUUGAACUCCUGACCUCAAGUGAUCCACCCACCUCGGCCUCCCAAAUUGUUAGGGAUAUCACGCAUGAGCCACUACAACUGGCCCUUGUGGGAAGGCACAGCCAUGUCUCCUGAAGUUAACAAGCACUAAGCUUUCCCAAGUAGUGAAAUGUCAAGCCCCUGCUUCUGUCACUUAUUUGUUCAUUCAGCAGAAAGUCACUGAGAGCCUUCUGUGCACCAGGCACAGUGCUGGGCAGUGAAAGAGACAGACAUGUGCCCUGGACCCAGGGAGAUGACAAGUGAUGGCUGUCAGGCCCAGACCCUGUUGUUUGUCUGCAGCCUCUUCCCUCAGGCAACUUGUUCUCUAUCAGGAGAAACGAAAUAAUUAUUAUCUGGAGAGGCAGGUGGGGGCGCUGCUCCUAGAAGACUGGGACAGCCUGGUAGAGGUUCUAGCUUGAUCAUGUGAGCAGUGGAAACCAUUUUAAGUAGGAGGUUAACAGGACCAAAAUAGCAUUUAAAAAAUUGUUUAUGGCCACUGUGAAGCCAGUUUCACCAGCGUCACUUGCCCAUGCUGGGCUGCCACCCAGCUAAUUCCUGGUCCUGCUCAUUUAGCCCAGCUCAGCUCACAUCACUUCCUCCAGAAACUAGAGAAGGGUAGAGCCCCUGACCAUCUUCACAGCAUUAGUCCUGAUAGCUGAAUCUUACGUCAGUUGUUAACAUCUGUGACCUGUGCAGGGAGAAUGGCAGGGCUGAGUUUCACCUACAUUGUUUCCCCAAUACCUACAGCAGAGCCAAGCACAGUGGGAACUUUCAGAAAGCACUGGUUGAAGGAACGCUGGAAUCCCUGGGACUUACUGCGUAGCAUGUAGUAGUUGCUCCUCUAGAAAAGUUUCACCUUAUGAAGUAUAGCAGGCUCUGAUGCUGGUGUCUGGUAGAAGAAGGUUACUCACAGUUCUGCUGCAGGCUCAGAAGUGGCCCUUUCAACCCUCCAGAGACAUGAGACUAGUGCAGUUCCGGGCACCCCACCUGGUGGGGCCUCACUUGGGCCUGGAGACAGGGAAUGGUGGAGGGGUUAUCAACCUCAAUGCCUUUGACCCCACACUCCCGAAGACGAUGACGCAGUUCCUAGAGCAGGGAGAGGCCACCCUCUCAGUGGCAAGAAGAGCCCUGGCUGCCCAGUUGCCAGUCCUACCACGGUCGGAGGUAACCUUCCUGGCUCCAGUCACACGACCAGAUAAGGUGGUGUGUGUGGGCAUGAAUUAUGUGGACCACUGCAAAGAACAGAACGUGCCCGUGCCCAAGGAGCCCAUCAUCUUCAGCAAGUUUGCCAGCUCCAUCGUGGGGCCCUAUGAUGAGGUGGUCCUCCCACCACAGAGCCAGGAGGUAGAUUGGGAAGUGGAGCUGGCCGUGGUCAUUGGAAAGAAAGGCAAGCACAUCAAGGCCACAGAUGCUAUGGCCCACGUGGCCGGCUUCACUGUGGCUCAUGACGUGAGUGCUCGUGACUGGCAAAUGAGACGUAAUGGGAAACAAUGGCUGCUGGGAAAAACCUUCGACACCUUCUGCCCUCUGGGCCCUGCCUUGGUGACCAAGGACAGUGUAGCAGAUCCACACAACUUAAAGAUCUGCUGCCGAGUGAAUGGGGAAGUGGUCCAGAGCGGCAACACCAACCAGAUGGUAUUCAAGACAGAGGACCUGAUAGCCUGGGUCUCCCAGUUUGUUACCUUUUACCCAGGGGAUGUCAUCCUAACUGGGACCCCCCCAGGUGUCGGUGUAUUCAGGAAACCUCCUGUCUUUCUCAAGGUCUCUGAAGGUCCAGAUAGCACUGAUGGCAAGCUUUGGGUCUGCACACUCUGGAAAGAAGAGAGAAGUGAAGGCUCUAGGGGGCAGCAGCCACCAGCAAACACCACUGCCUGCAGGAGCCUGGGCUGACUGGUUGGGACUCACCAAAGAUCCCUUCUUCCUGGGCGGUGGCCUGCAGGAACUGGAACAGCUGUUGGAGAGGAGAAGAAAAAGAAGACAUCAAAAAGAAAAUCUAGUGCUGGGUGGAUAUAGAGUAUGAAGAUGUGGAGCUGGGAAAACAGAGGAUGUGGUGGGAUGGGGAAGGAAAGGUUGUGGAAGGCCUGCACCCCGUCUCAGUUCCUCCACUGCUUCGUCCCAGAUUCUGUUUUUGUUUUCCUGAAUCAGACUUAGUCUCCCUCCAUUCUCCCGUCCCCUGUGUGCCCCCAUCCUGGUCCUGCCUCACUGGACAGCCUCUCCGCGGCCUUCCUCCUCCCUGCUCCAGAAUUCUACUUGGUGCCCCCCAACCCCACUCGACUCAUUGUCCACCUGGCCUCUGAGGCCAGGCACCCUCAUUCCCCUCUCCCACCCACCCCACCCAAGGAAGCCCAGCACAGACCAUCUCAUCUCACUCCACCAUCACUUCUUUGCCAAAUGCAUUUCCAAACACCCUCAUGAGCUUUGCUGAUCUCUUUGCCAUCUCUCCCUGCCCCACUCCGAUGGCUCCUCCUGCCUGGUGAAGACUGCCCUGGGUAUCCCAGAACUGAACCUGCAGCAGCCAGCACAGCUGACCUUGGGGCGAUAAGCAGCCAGGGAAAGGCUUUCUUAAAAAAAAACAAAAAACAAAACCAAUAACUCAGUAAGCAGAUUAAACAAAGGUAGAGACGGAGCCCUCCACCCCUCUCACACACUCAUCCUCACACCCAGCUAUACCACACCCCACAAAUGUUGCUUAUGUUUCCUUGGUCAUUCUGUCCAUCCUCCUGUCUGUCCAAAGCCAAGGACACUGCUCUACUCUAAAUUUUUUGUCCCGAAGCCCCCAAAUACUGCAACCCUGACCCAAUGCACGAAGCCACCCCAAAAUACAGCAGAGGACACCAGGACUUUCAUUUUCCCUCAGUAUGGCCCAUCCUUUGGGUAUGCCAACUCCAUGUCCACCAAGCACUGCAUGUAGGACAGGGCACAGUUUGGAGGCCUUGGUCCAGCCACUGCCCCAGACCCACCUUGGCUCUCUCCUCACUAACACCCGAGAAGCCCAGACUUCCCAGUGUUUAGCAACAGAUUAAACUCUAAGCCAACAACAACAGAACAGGGUGGAGUGAGUGGAAAGCAAAUGAAAUGUUAAAAAAAAAAAAAAAGCAAUACUUGCAUUCUCAUUAGUAGGAACAUGUGAGAUGAAGCAUGUUAUGUUAUUAGGCAUUCUCUUGAUUCGGUAAACACAAGCUGAAUAAAUUUAUAAAUAUCAGCAUUAAGCGAGAUUUAACGGGGAGCUGUUUAUCUUCUGCCUGUCAGGCAGGCGGCAACACUCUCCAUGUAUCACUCGCCAGCCGUGCAGUCCUCACUCUCUUGCCCAGGUAAGCUGGGGAAGAGCCUGCUGCCGCCCAGCUCUGGUUGUGGAAGGGCUGGCACCAAGGAGCUGCGAGCUUACCUCAACUCAUCUCACCUCACCAUGCCGGCUGCGAGGCGGCCCGUGCAGUCCGUGCGCAGGAGGUCACACUCCCAUGCUGCAUCCCAGCCCCUCCAGAAGCAGAGCAUGACCUGGGUGACUUUGAGGAUGCUAUUUAACCUCUCUAAGCUAAAGCUCCUCGACUGCAGCAUCAACAGAUCAGUGCCGACCUGUUAAGGCCGUCGAGAGCAUCAAAUGCUACUGUUCAGCAGGUGCCUGACACAUAGUAGGUCCACAAGCAAAUGAUUUUCCUGCUUGCAUCAUUUCUAGCACAGAGCUGGAGGAAAUGGCGAGGUGCAGGUGGCCGCUGGGCCCUGCUGUUCUACAUGGGAGCAAGACAGCUGCUAGGUGAAGGGGAAUGACCAGGCAGCCACAGGGAGGACAUGUGGCCUCAGGAAGCCUGGGUGUGUAUCCUGGUUCUGCUAGGAACACGUGUGGGGCUUUGUGUGGGUGACUCUCUGGCUCCCCAAGCCUCCCUUUCCUACUGUUAUAUCCUUAAAGUGCCUCUGAGGCCAAAGCCUUUGUGGCAAUUGUCAAAUGAGUCCAUAUGCAGUGAGUACCGUGUUGAGGGAGGACAAGGUCACCAAGAGCUGAGAAUGUUUCUCCGACUGAUGAGACCUAGAUAUUGGGUACAUGGAGGUCCCCGGUCCCUUUGUGAUUCCUGCAGCCUGUUGCCUCCUUGCCUGGACCCCGCCUCAGCUCAGAAAGCCAAUUCCCUAGAUUCCAAAGGCCUUCCCAGACCAAUUAGCAUGUCCUGCAGCUGUCAGCUCCCUGUGCCUAGCCUGGACCUCAGCUCAUGUCUAGCACCCAGUCUCCCAACCCCACACAUAUUCACAAAUAAAAGAAAAUAACAAAUGACAUGAAUUCUUCA